AGAUCGGAAGUGACGGAGACGUGCUAGCGCGUCGAAGGUAGCUCUAUGGUUUUCCUCGCGUUCUUGAGUCGGGAAAUGGCCGCUGUGUGGUUGCAACGGAGAUAAAUUCCCGGAACCGCGAUUCGGCGUGUCAGGAAUUCGAAUUUAGAGUUUAAUUUCUCAGAGCAUUCUCUCCAGGAAGAAUUUUUACAGUAUCUCAAAGACUUCACUUGACUUCUUGAUCCUGCAUAAAACCAAGGAGAAAAGAAAUGGGUCGCUCCAAUUCUAGAUCACAUUCUUCAAGGUCAAAGUCUAGAUCACAGUCUAGUUCUCGAUCAAGAUCAAGAUCUCAUUCUAGAAAGAAGCGAUACAGUUCUAGGUCUCGUUCCAGAACAUAUUCAAGGUCUCGUAGUAGAGAUCGUAUGUAUUCUAGAGAUUAUCGUCGCGAUUACAGAAAUAAUAGAGGAAUGAGACGACCUUAUGGGUACAGAGGAAGGGGUAGAGGGUAUUAUCAAGGAGGAGGAGGUAGAUAUCAUCGAGGUGGUUAUAGACCUGUCUGGAAUAGAAGGCACUCUAGGAGUCCUAGACGAGGUCGUUCACGUUCCAGGAGUCCAAAAAGAAGAUCCGUUUCUUCUCAAAGAUCCAGAAGCAGAUCUCGCCGGUCAUAUAGAUCUUCUAGGUCUCCAAGAUCAUCCUCUUCUCGUUCUUCAUCCCCAUAUAGCAAAUCUCCUGUUUCUAAAAGACGAGGGUCUCAGGAAAAACAAACCAAAAAAGCUGAAGGGGAACCCCAAGAAGAGAGUCCGUUGAAAAGUAAAUCACAGGAGGAACCGAAAGAUACAUUUGAACAUGACCCAUCUGAGUCUAUCGAUGAAUUUAAUAAGUCAUCAGCCACAUCCGGUGAUAUUUGGCCUGGCCUUUCAGCUUAUGAUAAUAGUCCUAGAUCACCCCAUAGUCCUUCACCUAUUGCUACACCACCUAGUCAGAGUUCAUCUUGCUCUGAUGCUCCCAUGCUCAGUACAGUUCACUCUGCAAAAAAUACUCCUUCUCAGCAUUCACAUUCCAUUCAGCAUAGUCCUGAAAGGUCUGGGUCUGGUUCUGUUGGAAAUGGAUCUAGUCGAUACAGUCCUUCUCAGAAUAGUCCAAUUCAUCACAUCCCUUCACGAAGAAGUCCUGCAAAGACAAUCGCACCACAGAAUGCUCCAAGAGAUGAGUCUAGGGGCCGUUCCUCGUUUUAUCCUGAUGGUGGAGAUCAGGAAACUGCAAAGACUGGGAAGUUCUUAAAAAGGUUCACAGAUGAAGAGUCUAGAGUAUUCCUGCUUGAUAGGGGUAAUACCAGGGAUAAAGAGGCUUCAAAAGAGAAAGGAUCAGAGAAAGGGAGGGCAGAGGGAGAAUGGGAAGAUCAGGAAGCUCUAGAUUACUUCAGUGAUAAAGAGUCUGGAAAACAAAAGUUUAAUGAUUCAGAAGGGGAUGACACAGAGGAGACAGAGGAUUAUAGACAGUUCAGGAAGUCAGUCCUCGCAGAUCAGGGUAAAAGUUUUGCUACUGCAUCUCACCGGAAUACUGAGGAGGAAGGACUCAAGUACAAGUCCAAAGUUUCACUGAAAGGCAAUAGAGAAAGUGAUGGAUUUAGAGAAGAAAAAAAUUAUAAACUUAAAGAGACUGGAUAUGUAGUGGAAAGGCCUAGCACUACAAAAGAUAAGCACAAAGAAGAAGACAAAAAUUCUGAAAGAAUAACAGUAAAGAAAGAAACUCAGUCACCUGAGCAGGUAAAGUCUGAAAAGCUCAAAGACCUCUUUGAUUACAGUCCCCCUCUACACAAGAAUCUGGAUGCACGAGAAAAGUCUACCUUCAGAGAGGAAAGCCCACUUAGGAUCAAAAUGAUAGCGAGUGAUUCUCACCGUCCUGAAGUCAAACUCAAAAUGGCACCUGUUCCUCUUGAUGAUUCUAACAGACCUGCUUCCUUGACUAAAGACAGGCUGCUUGCUAGUACACUUGUCCAUUCUGUCAAGAAGGAGCAAGAAUUCCGAUCCAUCUUUGACCACAUUAAGUUGCCACAGGCCAGCAAAAGCACUUCAGAGUCAUUUAUUCAACACAUUGUGUCCUUGGUUCAUCAUGUUAAAGAGCAAUACUUCAAGUCAGCUGCAAUGACCCUAAACGAGCGGUUCACUUCGUAUCAGAAAGCCACUGAAGAACAUAGUACUCGGCAAAAGAGCCCUGAAAUACACAGGAGAAUUGACAUCUCACCAAGUACCCUGAGGAAGCAUACCCGUUUAGCAGGGGAAGAGAGAGUUUUUAAAGAAGAAAAUCAAAAGGGAGAUAAAAAAUUAAGGUGUGACUCUGCUGACCUUCGGCAUGACAUUGAUCGCCGUAGAAAAGAAAGAAGUAAAGAACGGGGAGAUUCCAAGGGCUCCAGGGAAUCCAGUGGAUCAAGAAAGCAGGAAAAAACUCCAAAAGAUUACAAGGAAUACAAAUCUUACAAAGAUGACAGUAAACAUAAAAGAGAGCAAGAUCAUUCUCGAUCUUCAUCCUCUUCAGCAUCACCUUCUUCUCCCAGUUCUCGAGAAGAAAAGGAGAGUAAGAAGGAAAGAGAAGAAGAAUUUAAAACUCACCAUGAAAUGAAAGAAUACUCAGGCUUUGCAGGAGUUAGCCGACCACGAGGAACCUUUUUUCGAAUUAGAGGCAGAGGAAGAGCCAGAGGAGUUUUUGCUGGGACAAAUACUGGUCCAAACAACUCAAAUACUACUUUUCAAAAGAGACCGAAGGAAGAGGAAUGGGAUCCAGAAUAUACCCCAAAGAGCAAGAAGUACUUCUUGCAUGACGACAGAGAUGAUGGUGUGGAUUAUUGGGCCAAAAGAGGAAGAGGUCGUGGUACUUUUCAACGUGGCAGAGGGCGCUUUAACUUCAAAAAAUCAGGUAGCAGUCCUAAAUGGACUCAUGACAAAUACCAAGGGGAUGGGAUUGUUGAAGAUGAAGAAGAGACCAUGGAAAAUAAUGAAGAAAAGAAGGACAGACGCAAGGAAGAAAAGGAAUAAUAAAUAUGAAGUAAGAUUACAACAGAGCAGAACUUGCACCCACCAUUUUUUUUACCUGAUUUUUGUUUUCAAAUAAGAAUGUAAGCAUUUUACUUAAAUUUUACUGUUUGCAAGUAGUCUAUAGAAAUUUUGUUUUAAGUCUUCAAAUAUCUUGAGAAAUAGUAGACUGUAUGUUGAAAAUUGUACUGAAAUAAAGUAGAAAAUUGUUACGUACCAUAUUUGUAACUAUCAACUUUUAAAACUUUUAACGUUUUUGUUACAUGCAUUGUAAUUCUGCUUUGUCUAUAAGAUAUGGUCAAGUACAGCUCUGUGAAAGUUCUGAUUCUCUUCCUUCCCUGUUUGUCAAUGUUUUAUUCUGAAGUAAACGUUAGCUCUACAUAUAAAUCCUGGAACAGAAAUUGUUUAUAGAGACUACACUAAUUAUUUUAACUGUAUACAUCUGUUUAAUUUGAACACACUACAUCGUAGGGUGACUGAUUUUUGAAGUAUACCACAGACAAAAAGUUGUUACUAUGGUAAACUAAGCUAGUUUAACACUUGAGCAAAUGCUUAAGAAGGAAUUAAAAAAAAAAAGCUUUGCCAAUAGCUAAAAAGUACAAGCUAUUAAAAAUCAGAUUGAAAAGUUUUGAGAAAAUGUUAUUUUUACUGAAAGCAAGCAGUGGCCUAUAAAGAACAUUCUUAGGAGCCUUUUCUAUUUGCGUUCAAAACUGUGUGUUCUCUUUCUAUUCCUAUUUGAUAGUUUGAGUCAUGGUCUUAGAUAUUAGCUAUUUGUGAGAGGAAACUGGUUUGUAACAAUACUGCAAAUAGAAACCCCAUUUCUACUGAACAUCCUAGUUUUAAACAGAAGAAAAACUGUAAUCCUGGGGUUGGUAUGUAGGAGGUCUAUCCUGCAGAAUAAGUUGAUACAUUAGUACCUGAUUUCAUAUCUUACAUAUUUAUUUGAGCUGAACAUUAGUUUGUAGUGUAACUAUUAGUAAAAAUAGAGAAACACAGCAUACUGUUCAUUAAUAGUAUUUUAAAAAAAUUGUUUUUCAAAUGUCACCAAUAAAAGUUUUGGCAGGAAGCUUGUUGCGGCAUUGAUCUAACCUUUUUCCCCCCCAUUUCAGUUGCAGUUUUUGUAGAAUGGCUUUUUCUUUUUCCUCUUAAGAGUUCUAUUCUUCAGGUAGAUAAUUUUUCAAAUGUGAAUUAUCUUUUGUGUCUAUAUUGAUAGCUCUUAAAGGAGUGAAAAUCUAAAAUAGUAAAUUUCAAUGUUAAGUGUCUGCUUUAUGGGCAUAUAUAAAAGUAGACACAUUUCAUUUGUUAAUUUAGUUGUGUGUGUGUGUUAAAAGGAGCUAAUGCUUAUUCUGUUAAUGUAAACUUUUGAAGAUCUUAAGUGUAUUGCUCUUUCAUCUUAAACACUUUCGAGGAUUUGCAGUGCGUCUAGCACCUAGAUUACAGCCAGGAACAUUGGUUAAGAACUGUUGGAAACAAAACUAAAAGCAAACUCAACAUAUGUGAUGUUUAUGGCCCUCAGAUCCUUAGUAUUGUGUGAUUUUCCCCCGUUAACAUGUCUUUCUAAAAUUGUCUAUUAAAGCAGAGGAAAUACCUGCCAAAGGAAGUAUGUAUUGCAUUAAUCAGGGCAUAACUAAUAUUCUCCUGUUCAGAAUAAUACUUAUUUACGUGUGAAAGCAACAUGGAUGUGAUUCCCAACACAGAAUUUUCAUGACCCUUUUAUUGUAUACAAAUAAAUACCAUAACAGUUACUUGGUUAGACAUCAAAUCUGUGUGCAUGACUAUGUGCUUAUCCACUUAAGACAAUAGGUAAAAGGGGAUCUGAGAAAUUAUGUAAUAGGGAGUGGGAAUAAAACUACUUAAUUCCUGUGGGCAGGUUAUAUUUUAAGUUCAAAUGCAUUGCUUUAACCUUUGGUUACUUUUAUUCUGUUAAACAGAAUUGAAGAAAGAGUAUUAUACCAGAGUGUAGUAGGCUAGGGUGAUUGUAAGAACUCUGUAAUAGAAUGUCAUUGUGGAUGUUACCUUUUUCAGAUCCAAGCAUAUAAAAAGCCUGUAUAUUUUUUAAAAACACAUCUUAACUCCACGCUUUACGAUAUUAUAAAAGUUGAAUGGUUCCUCUUGGUAAGGAUAUUUGCUUACAAGUGCUAGGAAAUAACUCACUGAUACCUGCGUUAACAUACUUUGUUUUGCCUAGAGAGGGGCAAUAAAAAUGAACCAAAGGAUAUUUCCAGAAAGGAUUAAGAAAGCUGUUUAAGAAGGCCAUGACUCUUUAGGUGUGUAUGUGUACCUUUCAGCAUCCUAGGAAUUUUUAUACUAAAAGCAAAAUGUUUUUUCCAGUUAGUCUUCUUCAAGGAAUUACUAUUGUUCCUUUUGUCACAGGUAAAAUCAGUGUUGGGAAUUAUAAUUUGAGAAAAAUAUUACCCAGUAACAUUGAAUGUAGAUGGCUAAACGAUUCUUACUCAGUGUGAUGUAUAAUGAUGCAACAGGGACCCUUGUAAAUUGUCAUACGCCAAUAAAAUGUCACAAGUAAUAACUGCUGUUGUUUGUUUACCUGUGUCUAUUUCACACAUCUUAUUUCUGUGGCCUAUUUUAGAAUAUCAGCGCAUCUGUUAGGAAGAUUACUGGUGUGGUAAGGCUUGAUAAAUGCUUUAUAAACUCCCUCAAACCUUUCUUUACUGUUUUUUUGUUUUGUCUUGUUUUUGUUUUUGUUUUUGUUUUUGUUUUUGUUUUUGUUUUUCCCUUGUCUCCCCUGGGAAAAUGGGAAAUUUUACAGUUGGUAAAUCUAAGCCAAAAUUAUUUUGAAAUAAAGGAAUUCUGGAUGUCCAGUUUAGUCCUCGUUUUCUUACGUUAAUCUGGGACCUUAUCACCCAUAAUAUGGUGAUUACUUCUCUUUCUAAAAACAUAGUAGCUAGUAAAUAAGUAAAAAGAAUUGUCUUUUCAUUCACUUUAAGUAAGAUGUGGUAUAAUUCUUACCAUGUGCCAUCCUGUCAGUUUUAACAAAGCAUUUUCACAGAAAUUUGUGUACUAAGACAAACUGACACAUUUUGACUCAUACAAAUGGCAAAUUAGUCCUUAAAAAUUCUGUGAGAGAAAUAACUCUGUGUGUACAUACAUAUGCAUGUAAAGUGUUGUGUAAGAUCAUUGGUAGCUUAAUUAUACUGGAUAAUUGUAAUGUUAUAUACAAAUUUCUUAUAUAAAAGUAUGCUGCAUUAUUAACAUUUGUUUAACUUUUCUUAUUUUUCUUUUUCUGGGUUUCAACUGGAAUCCCAUUGGUGGGGAUGUACCUUAAGUUUCCUUGUGGAAUAAUAGACUUUCACAUCCAGAAAGAGAAGUUCAGAGGCCUUUCUCAAUUUACAGAGUUGAAGAGGAAAGGCAAAUGGAGGAAUAAACUUCAUUGUCAUUGGGAUUAAUUUGGCUAGACUCAAUCUCUUGAGCCUUAAAAUGAGAAAGUAAUAUCCAUUACAUGUUUAGAGUUCUCAAAUAGUUGAUACUAUUAUUAAAUGUUUCAAAUUUUAUUGGGGUAGAUACUAAAAAUUAGUACACUGUCCUAAUGAAGUUUAAAUGAACAAGUUUUACAUUUCUUAGGAUUCAGGAAUAUAUGGAAUCUAGUUGUAUUUAAUUGACUUGAGAGCCACAGAGAUUGUGUUGAUUUAUGAGCUGGACUCCUAUUGUUUUAGAAACAUGCAGUAAUGAUUAACUUGUGUCAAUGAUGGUAAUGAGACCAAACUUGUACAUUUAAUUAAGGGUACCAGUUCUUUUUAUGUUACUAGACUAUACCUUGGCCUUUAAAAAUGAAUCUCACUGAUUAAAGAGAACAGGCAUUAUUAGGAUAGCAUUCCACCACAACUAGAAACAUUCAAAUAAUGUGUCUUAAUUGUAAUCUGUAUAUAGGAAAAUUUUUCCUAUGGAUAUUUUUGGUGUUUUACCACAGUGAACUGAUUUGUAGCACUUAUGAAGUGCAGAAGGUAAUAUUCUUGAAAAUAGAAAAAGGUUGGGUGAGCAGGCUUUAAUGCCUUUCCCCCAAGAAUAUACAUCGAAUUUUUCUUAAUCUUUUGGGGUUGGCCAGCUUCCAGAUUUCAUUAAUAAUGAGCUCUGCCUUUAAUAAAAGUACAUGAUCAUAGCUACACUGUAUGUUUAGGUGGUGUGAAAUGAUUUAUAAUCACAGCUUGAACUGUGUUUGCUUGGUACUGUCAUAGUGAUUACAAAUUUCAUGGAAUGCGAAGAGCAACAAUAAAUAAAAAAUACCACUCACCCUCCAGAAUAGUGGAUUAUUUGCUACCUUGAGUCCUUCACUAUGGAAAAUAAUUUUUCAGUCUCAUUUGUACUAGAAGGGAAAACUAAACUUUCUGUUGAGUUCUCAGGAUACUUGUAAGGUGGCCGUGAAAAAGAAUGUUAAAUGCACUUUGAAUUAUUUAUUUAUUUAUUUAUUUAUUUAUUUAUUUAUUUAUUGAGAUGGAGUCUUACCCAGACUAGAGUGCAGUGGCUCGAGCUC